GUGGCCUCGAUCACCACCGAGAGCUGACGGCCGCCCGGAUUCCCGCCCUCAGAGAAUCCUGGCCCCCAGUCGUUCCAAGACCCUUUACGGACUGCAGCUUAAAGGAACCGGCCUCUGCCAUUGAGACCAAACUGACAGAGGAACUGGUCACUCUUCUGUUCUUUCCAGAGAGGAGCUUAGCCAGGGACUUCUGCCCUUCCUGGGCCCGGGCCUCGGGGGCGAUUCCGGCAGGUGGUCCAUUAUGGCUGACAUGCAAAAUCUGGUAGAAAGAUUGGAGAGGGCAGUGGGCCGCCUGGAGGCAGUAUCUCAUACCUCUGACAUGCACCGUGGGUAUGCAGACAGUCCUUCAAAAGCAGGAGCAGCUCCAUAUGUGCAGGCAUUUGACUCGCUGCUUGCUGGUCCUGUGGCAGAGUACUUGAAGAUCAGUAAAGAGAUUGGGGGAGACGUGCAGAAACAUGCGGAGAUGGUCCACACAGGUUUGAAGUUGGAGCGAGCUCUGUUGGUUACAGCUUCUCAGUGUCAACAGCCAGCAGAAAAUAAGCUUUCCGAUUUGUUGGCACCCAUCUCAGAGCAGAUCAAAGAAGUGAUAACCUUUCGGGAGAAGAACCGAGGCAGCAAGUUGUUUAAUCACCUGUCAGCUGUCAGCGAAAGUAUCCAGGCCCUGGGCUGGGUGGCUAUGGCUCCCAAGCCUGGCCCUUAUGUGAAAGAAAUGAAUGAUGCCGCCAUGUUUUAUACAAACCGAGUCCUCAAAGAGUACAAAGAUGUGGAUAAGAAGCAUGUAGACUGGGUCAAAGCUUAUUUAAGUAUAUGGACAGAGCUGCAGGCUUACAUUAAGGAGUUCCAUACCACCGGACUGGCCUGGAGCAAAACGGGGCCUGUGGCAAAAGAACUGAGCGGACUGCCAUCUGGACCCUCUGCCGGAUCAUGUCCUCCUCCCCCUCCACCAUGCCCCCCUCCUCCCCCAGUCUCUACCAUUUCAUGCUCAUAUGAGUCUGCUUCCCGCUCAUCACUGUUCGCGCAGAUUAAUCAGGGGGAGAGCAUUACACAUGCCCUGAAACAUGUAUCUGAUGACAUGAAGACUCACAAGAACCCUGCCCUGAAGGCUCAGAGUGGUCCAGUACGCAGUGGCCCCAAACCAUUCUCUGCACCUAAACCCCAAACCAGCCCAUCCCCCAAACGAGCCACAAAGAAGGAGCCAGCUGUACUUGAACUGGAGGGCAAGAAGUGGAGAGUGGAAAAUCAGGAAAAUGUUUCCAACCUGGUGAUUGAGGACACAGAGCUGAAACAGGUGGCUUACAUAUACAAGUGUGUCAACACGACAUUGCAAAUCAAGGGCAAAAUUAACUCCAUUACAGUAGAUAACUGUAAGAAACUUGGCCUGGUAUUCGAUGACGUGGUGGGCAUUGUGGAGAUAAUCAACAGUAAGGAUGUCAAAGUUCAGGUAAUGGGUAAAGUGCCAACCAUAUCCAUCAACAAAACAGAUGGCUGCCAUGCUUACCUGAGCAAGAAUUCCCUGGAUUGUGAAAUAGUCAGUGCCAAAUCUUCCGAGAUGAAUGUCCUCAUUCCUACAGAAGGCGGUGACUUUAAUGAAUUCCCAGUUCCUGAGCAGUUCAAGACCCUAUGGAACGGGCAGAAGUUGGUCACCACAGUGACAGAAAUUGCUGGAUAAGCGAAGUGCCACUGGGUUCUUUGCCCUCCCUUCACACCAUGGGAUAAAUCUGUAUCAAGACGGUUCUUUUCUAGAUUUCCUCUACCUUUUUGCUCUUAAAACUGCUUCUCUGCUCUGAGAAGCACAGCUACCUGCCUUCACUGAAAUAUACCUCAGGCUGAAAUUUGGGGUGGGAUAGCAGGUCAGUUGAUCUUCUGCAGGAAGGUGCAGCUUUUCCAUAUCAGCUCAACCACGCCGCCAGUCCAUUCUUAAGGAACUGCCGACUAGGACUGAUGAUGCAUUUUAGCUUUGAGCUUUUGGGGGUUAUUCUACCAACAAACAGUCCAUUGGAAAGAAAACAGUCCCUGGAAUUAACAGAUCAGAAUGUUCACACUGGUUAAUCUUUUUUUAACAAUGAGCAUGAAGGUAGCAGAAGCUGGUGUGUUUCCAGAUGGUUCUUCUAACCAAACUAAUUUUUCACUGUUGACAAGCGAGGCAAGGGUUGCACUGGACCAAAGGCUGAGGCUUGGCCAUCUAGCAUUCCAUACAAAAUUGUUUCCUAUAAGCAUUCCUUUUAUUCUCUAUUCUAUCCUGGGUCUGCCUCAACCGUGAGAUAGGAGAGUCUCUGGUACUAGCUGCUGUAGCAGUGCCCUUCAUCCAGGGCAGUUAAUGGAGUCUUGGACCCUUUCUUUCUCUGGGAUCCCUGCCCAGCACCUUCCUAUAGAGAUGACUUUAAAAGGAAAAAAAAAAAAAAAAAAACCCACAUGAUUUCAAGGAGUCUGGCAUUCCUGAAUCCUUCUUCCCUGCCAGGUGCCUGUCACCUGUCUUCACUGCCUCCUUUUCCCUGUCAUGCUCAUCAGCUUAUGGCUUCUGUCUAAGCACCUGAACAGAGGACUGAAACCUCCACUGCAGGCUGGUUUUAGGUCUUGAAUUAUGUAAGAAUCUUGCACAGCACUGCUAAUGUAAAUUUCAGUUGUUUUUCCCUCUAGGACAAACACUUACCAAAAUAUGCAACUUUUUUUUGGUGGGAAGAGAGAUUGUCCUGUGAUUUCUACCCAUUUCCUGAGGCCUGUGGAAAUAAACCUUUAUGUACUUAAAGUUAUACAGAAAAUAGAAUAAAGUUAAUACCAAACUUG